AGUGGUCCCCAGGAACCCUCGACAGGGCCAGGGCGUCUCUCUCGUCCAGCAAGGGCAGGGACGGGCCACAGGCCAAGGGCAGCAGUCAGGCCUGCUCUGUCUGUGAACGCUCCCGGCUUGGCCUCGGCUGAUGGGCCCUCACGCCUGAAGCGGGCAGGAAGCUCCGGGAUGGAUUUCGGGUCUUUGGAGACCGUGGUGGCCAACUCUGCCUUCAUCGCCGCCCGAGGCAGCUUUGACGGCAGCAGCUCCCAACCCUCCCGGGACAAGAAGUACCUGGCCAAGCUCAAGCUGCCCCCGCUGUCCAAGUGUGAGUCCCUCCGCGACAGCCUCAGCCUGGAGUUUGAGAGUGUGUGCUUGGAGCAGCCCAUCGGCAAGAAGCUCUUUCAGCAGUUCCUACAAUCGGCAGAGAAGCACCUGCCGGCCCUGGAGCUCUGGAAAGACAUCGAGGACUAUGACACGGCAGACAAUGACCUCCAGCCACAGAAGGCCCAGACCAUCCUGGCCCAGUACCUGGACCCCCAGGCCAAACUCUUCUGCAGCUUCCUGGAUGAGGGGAUAGUGGCGAAGUUUAAGGAGGGGCCUGUGGAGAUCCAGGACGGGCUCUUCCAGCCCCUGCUGCAGGCCACCCUGGCACACCUGGGCCAAGCCCCCUUCCAGGAGUACCUGGGCAGCCUGUACUUCCUGAGGUUCCUGCAGUGGAAGUGGCUGGAAGCCCAGCCCAUGGGGGAGGACUGGUUCCUGGACUUCAGGGUCCUAGGGAAAGGGGGCUUCGGGGAGGUGUCGGCCUGCCAGAUGAAGGCGACCGGCAAGCUGUAUGCCUGCAAGAAGCUGAACAAGAAGCGGCUGAAGAAGAGGAAGGGCUACCAGGGUGCUAUGGUGGAGAAGAAGAUUCUGAUGAAAGUACACAGCAGGUUCAUCGUGUCUCUGGCCUAUGCGUUUGAAACCAAAGCCGACCUCUGUCUGGUGAUGACCAUCAUGAACGGAGGUGACAUCAGGUACCACAUCUACAACGUGAAUGAGGAGAACCCUGGCUUCCCGGAGCCGCGCGCCCUCUUCUACACGGCGCAGAUCAUCUGCGGCCUGGAGCACCUGCACCAGAGGCGGAUCGUCUACCGCGACCUCAAGCCCGAGAACGUGCUGCUGGACAAUGACGGCAAUGUCCGGAUCUCUGACCUUGGGCUGGCCGUGGAGCUGCUGGACGGACAGAGCAAGACCAAGGGCUACGCAGGGACCCCAGGUUUCAUGGCCCCCGAGCUCCUGCAGGGCGAGGAGUACGACUUCUCCGUGGACUACUUUGCCCUGGGGGUCACCCUGUAUGAGAUGAUUGCGGCCAGAGGACCCUUCCGAGCCCGUGGAGAGAAGGUGGAGAACAAGGAGCUGAAGCACCGGAUCAUCUCAGAGCCCGUGAAGUACCCUGAUAAGUUCAGCCAGGCCAGCAAGGACUUCUGCGAGGCGCUGCUGGAGAAGGACCCGGAGAAGCGCCUGGGGUUCAGAGAUGAGACCUGCGACAAGCUCCGUGCCCACCCCCUCUUCAAGGACCUUAACUGGAGGCAGCUGGAGGCUGGGAUGCUGAUGCCCCCUUUCAUCCCAGACUCCAAAACUGUCUACGCAAAGGAUAUUCAGGACGUGGGUGCCUUUUCCACCGUCAAAGGUGUGGCCUUUGACAAAACAGACACAGAAUUCUUUCAGGAAUUUGCCACUGGCAACUGCCCCAUCCCCUGGCAGGAGGAGAUGAUCGAGACGGGCAUCUUUGGCGAGCUGAACGUGUGGCGCUCGGACGGUCAGAUGCCGGACGACAUGAAGGGCAUCUCCGGGGGCUCCAGCUCCUCGUCCAAGUCAGGGAUGUGUCUGGUUUCCUAGGUGACGCCCCAGAGUCCACGUGGAGGAAAAGGACCCAUACGGCUCGAUGGGGGCCGCCUGCCUCCGUGGUGCCAGCCUGGGGUCUGCUAGCAAGGGGACACGUGGUUCCCUCCACCCAGGUCCCCAUCACGCCAUCUCCUUGCGGCCCAAGGAGGAGAAAGCCCACAUCGGCCUGAGCCGCCAGACGCACAUGCUGGUGCCGUGAGCCCCCGACUGCAUAUUUCACGUCUUUUGCUCCAUCUCACUGAGAAGACAUAAGAUGCUCUCCAGAGGGAGUAAGCCAAAAAUCUACAAACUCUUAGGGAGCCUCCUGCAUUGGUGAUUGACCAACCGUGUGGUCAGGGGCAGAGACUCGGUUUUGGCCUCCCAAGACCUUAGCCAUUGGCUUCCCAGAGCCACGCUCCUCAGCGGGAGGUGCACGGUGGCCAGGUCAGGGGUCAGUGAACCCUGGCCGCAGCCCCUGGCCCCACUGGGGAGGGCUGGACCUCGCCCCCCCCAGGUCCCUCUGUGCAGGCUCCUGACUUCCAGGGUGCCCGGGCCCUGUGCUGGUGGCCUGCACGCCACAUGGUCCCCUGCACCCUGCGGCGCCGUGGUCCUCUGCACACUGGGGCACCAUGGUCCCCUGCACUCCGGGGUGCCAUGGUCCACAUCUGCCAGGCGCAGGCUCUGUUGGGCUGUUGGGAGGAGGGGAGCGGGUGUGGAGUCUGGGGGUCUCAGUGCAUCUUGGGGUCUCCUUAUCUCAGGGUGUCCAGCUGACGGCAGCUGGUGCAAAGUUCCCACCCCUGAGCUGGGGAGCUGAAAAUGUUUUCUGUCUUGACCCUGAGUCCCGGAAGCACCUCAGCUGCUCUUGGCGGGCAAAGCCAGGACCGUUUGCUCUCUGACCCUCCUCCCCACUGGGGCUGGUCCGUCUCAUCUCCCAGGGGACACUUCAGGCCACGGGCCUUGUGCAUAGGGACAGAGCUCCUUGCUGCAACCCCUCUCUGUGUUCCCAGUAGCAGCAGCACUGGAGUCCUAAAGCCAUAGCCCGGGAAGACACUCACAGCCCACCUUCUCAUACAGCUCGGCCCCACCCACAAUGCACCUGGCAUUUCCAACUGCACUUUGAACACUGAAGGUUCCCCAAAUGCUUUGUGUGUUUUAACUGCAGGAAGUUAGUUCUGUUGCAACUGCCUCCAGGACACACUCCCUCUUGAGGGCCGGCGGUGCUGGCCUGGGUUCCAUGGCCUCAGCAGCCGGCUCAGAGGGAGUGCAUCCAAGCCGCAGGGAAGCAGUGGUGAUGGGCGGCCUGAGGACUCCUUUCCAGAGAGGGCCUCUGAGCUCCUUUUAGGAAAGAACUUCCUUUGAGCCCCGGCCACUGUUGUACCAGUGGGAGAAGAAGCCUGACCCUGCCACAUGUGGUCACGGGGAGAGAAGAUGGUAGGACGUCCCCGUGAGCCUUGGGGCAGAGCUGGUGGUAGAAAGAAGCCCUGUCUACUCUAAUUUGGUGAGAGGGGCCGCGGCAAGUGGCUGAUGAUGUGACUGAUGGAGACAGGGUGGCUUGGGAAGGUCCCACUUGGGGGUGUCACGUCCUGCAGGGAGUGGAAGAGAUGGAUCCUCCGUAGCCUGGACUGGUGGGUCUCGGCCUCUCUCCCAGAAAUGGCAGAGACAGCUGCCUGAGAGUCAGUGCUGCAGUGGGCAGGGCCUAUGCCCUCACAGUCCUCAGGCUGCCAGGUCGUCCUCUUCCUGUUGGGGAGAAGAGGACCCUGGCAAUCCACAAUUUUGGAGAUUUGCUGGCUGCAGCCAAAAUGGGGACCCAACUCCCUCCUAUGUGGUUUUAGAGCUUCUGGAGGGAAGAUAGGCCACGCCCCUGGGUGAGGAGCACGUCUUCCCACAGAUCCUAAGUCGGCCACACCCUGGGUGAGGAGCACGUCUUCCCAUAGGUCCCACGUCAGCCACACCCUGGGUGAGGAGCACGUCUUCCCAUAGAUCCCACAUCGGCCACACCCUGGGUGAGGAGCAUGUCUUCCCAUAGAUCCCACGUCGGCCACACCCUGGGUGAGGAGCACGUCUUCCCAUAGAUCCCACAUCGGCCACACCCUGGGUGAGGAGCAUGUCUUCCCAUAGAUCCCACGUCGGCCACACCCUGGGUGAGGAGCACGUCUUCCCAUAGAUCCCACGUCGGCCACACCCUGGGUGAGGAGCAUGUCUUCCCAUAGAACCCACGUCGGCCACACCCUGGGUGAGGAGCACGUCUUCCCACAGAUCUCAACAGAACUCCACAUCGUCUGGUUUUGUGGAGACUUUCAUAUGUCCUGUCAAGUUGCCUCAUGCACCUGCAGACUGUUCUUGGGAAGCAAACCUGGACUGCAAAAUAAACCUCCCGGCCUCCUCCUG